GAAGAAGGCCCCUCGGCCUCAGCAGAGCGCUAUCCUCCACUGGUUCCCCGGGUUCCCCGGCUUGCUACCGGGCUGCUCCGUGCAUCUUUCCCCCCAGGCGUCAGGAACUGCGCCCUCAUGGCGGAGGUGAAGGUGAAGGUGCAGCCGCCUGACGCGGAUCCGGUCGAAAUAGAAAACAGGUAAACCAGUGAGGCUCCGGCUUGGCACUCCAUCAGGCGCCCAGUCAUUUGGGCAGCUGGACCCCUUCUCCGGGAUCCCUUGGGAGUGGCCGGAGCGGGUUAGGAUUAUAGAAUUAUGUCACCAGUUCCCUCAUGGAAUCACAGACCAAGUAAUUCAGAAUGAAAUGCCUCAUAUAGAAGCCCAGCAGCGGGCAGUAGCCAUCAAUAGGUUGUUGUCUAUGGGUCAGUUGGAUCUCUUAAGGAGCAAUACGGGCCUUUUAUAUAGAAUAAAGGACUCUCAGAAUGCUGGUAAAAUGAAGGGAUCCGAUAACCAAGAAAAACUAGUAUAUCAAAUCAUAGAGGAUGCAGGAAAUAAAGGAAUAUGGAGCAGAGAUAUCCGCUAUAAAAGUAAUUUGCCAUUAACAGAAAUCAACAAAAUUCUGAAGAAUCUGGAAAGUAAAAAGCUUAUCAAAGCUGUUAAGUCUGUAGCAGCCUCAAAAAAGAAGGUGUAUAUGCUCUAUAACCUGCAGCCAGACCGGUCUGUGACUGGUGGAGCCUGGUACAGUGACCAGGAUUUUGAAUCUGAAUUUGUAGAGGUGCUUAACCAACAGUGUUUUAAAUUCCUACAGUCCAAGGCAGAAACAGCACGAGAAAGCAAACAGAACCCAAUGAUACAAAGAAAUAGUUCAUUUGCCUCAUCACAUGAAGUGUGGAAAUAUAUCUGCGAAUUGGGAAUCAGUAAGGUAGAGUUAUCCAUGGAAGACAUUGAAACCAUCCUGAAUACACUCAUUUAUGAUGGAAAAGUGGAGAUGACGAUUAUUGCUGCAAAAGAAGGCACAGUUGGCAGUGUAGAUGGACACAUGAAACUGUACAGGGCAGUCAAUCCAAUCAUCCCUCCCACAGGUUUGGUCCGGGCACCCUGUGGACUCUGCCCGGUUUUUGAUGACUGCCACGAAGGUGGUGAGAUUUCACCAUCUAACUGUAUUUACAUGACAGAGUGGCUCGAAUUUUAAUAGAGAGCUAUGAACUUUAUUGACAUUUUGCAAAUGAAGUUACUUAGGGAGCAGAUAAUUUAAUUCAUGAUGGAACACGAAAUCUCCUUGAAAGCAAACUUCACAAUAAUGGACGUAGACUUGCUGCUAUGAAAACAUAUUUUUUUUAUUUAUGAAGACUAAAUUUAUAUUGGUAAAAUAGCCAGUAGAAUAUGAAAGAAAUAAGGUUAGUAGUGAAAUUCAUUCUUCAAUAAAUAAAACACUUUGAAACUCCGGAGGACCACAUCUUUCAAGACUUCUGAUGGGUCAAGGAAAAAGAUGCCAACAUACCCGUAUUUACCAAGUACUAUGAUAAUGGCUAGAGUAUAAAAAUGUUCUUUUUAAAGUUAUUUAUUAAGUUCUUCAUUGGAAGUUUUUUUUUAUAUCUGGUUCACUACCACCAUUUUCUGUUUCCUACUUUCUCAGUGGUUUCAUUGAAAAGAAAUUAGAAGGGGUUAAAGGCAGGAAUAGCAAAGAGUGCAAACUUGGGGUAUGACUGGGGGAGAGUGGAACAUGCCUUUUCCGCACAAUAUUAAUUCCUUUUUGUAUCAGAAAUGUUCUUUUAGGAGAUUAUGCUACCAUACUUACUUCAAACCCAAUGACUACUGUCAAGGACAUAUUUUCAGUACAUAAAUACUAUCAUUUUCAUUCUAAAGAAUAUUUUCACUGUUCCUUCUUUCUUAAAGUCUUAUGUUUCACUCUUUAACUCAAAUGUAUUCUUUGUUAGAAUUUACCCUAGAUUCUUAUUUAAUGUCUGCAGUAGACUGAAUGUUUGUGUGCCCCCAGAAUUCUAAUGUUGAAAUCUCAUUUCCAAUGUGAUGGUAUUUGGAGGUGGGGCUUUUGGUAAGUGAUAGGUCAGGAGAGUAACAGCGCUCAUGAAUGGGAUUAGUGCCCUUAUAUAAAGAGACCCAGAGAGCUCCAUCACCCCUUCUGCCAUGUGAAAGGGAGAAGACAAACAUCCACGAACCAGGAAGUGGGUCCUCACCAGAAAACAAAUCUGUAAGCACCUUGAUCUUGGACUUCUCAGCCUCCAGAAUUGUGAGAAAUAAAUUUCUGUUGUUGAUAAACCA